AUGGGGCUUUGGCGGGUCUGGGGGCGGCAGUGCUUCUGUGGGAGCCUCAGGGAGGGCUCAUCCUUGGAAUCCACCAGGGUGUACCUGGAGAGCCUGGUCUAUACCCGGUGCUCUGCUACACCCCAUGGCCUGGCCAUGACCUCCCUGCCUCCAGAGCAGCCCUGGCCCAGGGAAGAAGCUGUCUCUGCAUCGAAUGAUAGGUGGAAAAUGGAAGUGGGGAUGAUAGCUCUGAAAAGGAGUCAAGGAGGAGAGGACUGGAUUGCAAAACAAGUGUCCCCUGCCUUCUGGCUGGGGGACAUCCUCUACUUCCAAGCCCAGACAUACACCUGCUGCCACAAGCCCCUGAGAUUCUCAGGGGACCCUGGGAAGGAAGAGGGGCUGCCCCUGCAAAGGGCCAGGGCCCUGGCCCAUGGUUGCUUCCCCCAGCAGUUAAACCGGCGGUUGGCGCUGGUUUUUUCCAGGGCAGGAUUCUGGGAGACGGAGGAGCAGACGCCAGCAUUUCGCCCCCGGCACCUCCAGCGGGCUGCGCUGACCUGGCGGGACCGGAAAAAGAAAUUCCCGGGCGAUGAUGAGGCACCAGGGGUGAAGCGGACAUGGGCUGCUGGAGCGGGAAUGAGGGGGCGCCAGUGGCUCCGGAAACGGGUUGAGGUUGUCUGCACUGGCCGCUCCGCAAACACAGUGUGUGCGGGCGUCAGGGCAGCAGGUCUGGUAGAGAAAAGUCCACCGCCAUCCCUCUCCCGAGUGGGGCGGUUAAGGCUCCAGGGGCAGAGACCUAACUGCGCCUUGUGUGUAGUGCUAAGGGGGCUUCCUGAGGAUGCCUUCAACCUUAAAGGCGAUGGCAGGAGUUGGCUGGCUGAAGUACAGUUUGUGUACCAGGGGUUGGGAGGCAACGGUGGGAGGCGUGUGUCUUCAGACAGGGAACAGCAUGUGCAGAGACUUCAGAGGUUUCGGUUCUGUGGUGAUCUGGACUGUCCUGACCGGGUCCUGGCAGAGAUCAGCACGCUGGCCAAGAUGUCCUCUGUGAAGUUGCAGCUGCUCUGCAGCCAGGUACUAAAGGAGCUGCUGGGACAGGGAAUUGAUUAUAAGAAGAUCCUGAAACUCACAGCUGAUGCCAAGUUUGAGUCAGGCGAUGUGAAGGCCACAGUGGCAGUGCUGAGUUUCAUCCUCUCCGGUGCGGCCAAGCACAGUGUCGAUGGCAAAUCCUUGGCCAGUGAACUGCAGCAGCUGGGGCUGCCCAAAGAGCACGCGGCCAGCCCGUGCUGCUGUUAUGAGGAGAAGCAAAGCCCCUUGCAGAAGCACUUGCGGGUCUGCAGCCUACGCAAAGUACAGAGGAACCUGGUGCCGGCCGCCGUCAACCCCUAUGUGAUGAUCUUUCUACCCGCCCUCUUUCGUGUCUUGGUGCUGGCUGCUGUCUUUGGCCAGGUGGUGGGUUCAAAGACCAUUCCUGGGUUCCACCACCGCCAAGCCUCAAUGGUGUCUCGAUGGUCACAGGAACUGCUGGGGCUUUCUAGGUUAAGACCCUUGCCUAUCCCGGUGUUCCUCCCUGCAGUAGGGGGCUGCAGGGGUCAGCCUCAGUCUCUGCCUUGGGAGCCUGCCUUACCUUGCCUGAACUCAAGCGAUCUGCCUGCCUUGGACUCCCAAAGUGCUGCAAUUAUAGGCGUGAGCCACUGCACCCAGCCCAGCCUUGACUUUGAAAUAUAUGUUGUACAUCCAGACAGCAGUGAACUCUGGGGGAACACCAAAGAUGAGGAGAAUGAGAGAAGAGAUACCUCCAAUUAAAGGAGUUAGGAAGAGAUGCUUGAACUUAUGUUUUAAAAAGUCAAUGCAGGUUGGGCACAGUGGCUCGCACCUGUACACACAGCACCUUGGGAGGCUGAAGUGGGUGAACGGCUGGAGCCUAGAAGUCUGAGACCACCCUGGGCAACAUGGCAAAACCCCGUCUGUACACAAAAUACAAUAAUUA